GUGACAUCACAUCCACUAACCAAAUGGGGUGGUGUGAGUAUCUCCUAUAAAAUAAAAGCUCUCCUGAUGGCCUGUUCCUGCACAUUUCCUGAGGACGCCCUCGAUCACAAGCAGCUUGCUGGAUGAAUAAAGGAAAGAAGGUUUAUAUACACUAAUAAUAGAAAUGUUUUGGGAUGGUUCAUGAUUUCGAAAAGCUUCAGAGAAAAUAAAGAUGCUUAAUGUUAGAGUACAAAACAUUCUCCCUGCAGUCUCACGAACUGUGAACAAAAACUGAAGUGAAAACUCAUAGUGCAUAACUCGUCAAUACUCCUGUGAUCGUAUAACCAUCAGCAAGAAAACAAAUUUGAUUGAGCCCCCAUCCAGUCCUCUUUGCGUGGAAUCAGACCUCUUUUGCAGUGGAAAGGAGCAGAGAAUGUGACUUUCCUGAACAACAGGAGCAAGAAUCAAUGCCAGAUUCUCUUCUCUAAAAAUAAUCAAUUUGUUACUACAGCCGCAUGAGCCUUAAUUCAUUUCAGCAUCAACUCUGAAGUCUAAAAUUCAAAGCUUCUUCUAAGCAUUUUUAAAAUCAGAUAUGGGUGAGACUCCAAGCAAAAAUCCAUGCUGAAACUAAAUAUCCCUCCAGCUAUGAAACUGUGAAACUAGAUAAGACUACAUCGGGGAAGGAUUAAGGCUCUAGCACUGCAGCAGGAAGUUAAAUGUCUGCAGUCACACUGCCCAUGCCAACUGUGGAUCAGAUCUUCUGGCCGUGGGGUCCAAUGCAUUGCAAAGGACUGGAUCUUGUGUACAGUGUCUCUCUCCACUUUUUUGCUGCAGCUCUGAUGGUUCAACUCUGCCAAAAGAUGGAUCUUUAAUGAUUAGCACUACACACUGACCAACUCAGAAGAAGGAGCCACACCACCUGUGACUCCAGCCCUGACUUCUGCUCUGGACCAGUGUUUCCAUAACAGGGACUUCAAAAUCACUGUGAUUUGAAGCCUUUUUGAACAUGAAGAUGUUACUCCUGCUGCAUUGCCUUGGGGUGUUUCUGUCCUGUUCUGGACACAUCCAGGAUGAGCACCCCCAAUAUCACAGCCCUCCGGAUGUGGUGAUUCCUGUGAGGAUAACUGGCACCACCAGAGGCAUGACACCUCCAGGCUGGCUCUCCUAUAUCCUGCCCUUUGGAGGCCAGAAACACAUUAUCCACAUAAAGGUCAAGAAGCUUUUGUUUUCCAAACACCUCCCUGUGUUCACCUACACAGACCAGGGUGCUAUCCUUGAGGACCAGCCAUUUGUCCAGAAUAACUGCUACUAUCAUGGUUAUGUGGAAGGGGACCCAGAAUCCCUGGUUUCCCUCAGUACCUGUUUUGGGGGUUUUCAAGGAAUAUUACAGAUAAAUGACUUUGCUUAUGAAAUCAAGCCCCUAGCAUUUUCUACCACGUUUGAACAUCUGGUAUACAAGAUGGACAGUGAGGAGAAACAAUUUUCAACCAUGAGAUCCGGAUUUAUGCAAAAUGAAAUAACAUGCCGAAUGGAAUUUGAAGAAAUUGAUAAUUCCACUCAGAAGCAAAGUUCUUAUGUGGGCUGGUGGAUCCAUUUUAGGAUUGUUGAAAUUGUAGUCGUCAUUGAUAAUUAUCUGUACAUUCGUUAUGAAAGGAACGACUCAAAGUUGCUGGAGGAUCUAUAUGUUAUUGUUAAUAUAGUGGAUUCCAUUUUGGAUGUCAUUGGUGUUAAGGUGUUAUUAUUUGGUUUGGAGAUCUGGACCAAUAAAAACCUCAUUGUAGUAGAUGAUGUAAGGAAAUCUGUGCACCUGUAUUGCAAGUGGAAGUCGGAGAACAUUACGCCCCGGAUGCAACAUGACACCUCACAUCUUUUCACAACUCUAGGAUUAAGAGGGUUAAGUGGCAUAGGAGCUUUUAGAGGAAUGUGUACACCACACCGUAGUUGUGCAAUUGUUACUUUCAUGAACAAAACUUUGGGCACUUUUUCAAUUGCAGUGGCUCAUCAUCUAGGUCAUAAUUUGGGCAUGAACCAUGAUGAGGAUACAUGUCGUUGUUCACAACCUAGAUGCAUAAUGCAUGAAGGCAACCCACCAAUAACUAAAUUUAGCAAUUGUAGUUAUGGUGAUUUUUGGGAAUAUACUGUAGAGAGGACAAAGUGUUUGCUUGAAACAGUACACACAAAGGACAUCUUUAAUGUGAAGCGCUGUGGGAAUGGUGUUGUUGAAGAAGGAGAAGAGUGUGACUGUGGACCUUUAAAGCAUUGUGCAAAAGAUCCCUGCUGUCUGUCAAAUUGCACUCUGACUGAUGGUUCUACUUGUGCUUUUGGGCUUUGUUGCAAAGACUGCAAGUUCCUACCAUCAGGGAAAGUGUGUAGAAAGGAGGUCAAUGAAUGUGAUCUUCCAGAGUGGUGCAAUGGUACUUCCCAUAAGUGCCCAGAUGACUUUUAUGUGGAAGAUGGAAUUCCCUGUAAGGAGAGGGGCUACUGCUAUGAAAAGAGCUGUCAUGACCGCAAUGAACAGUGUAGGAGGAUUUUUGGUGCAGGCGCAAAUACUGCAAGUGAGACUUGCUACAAAGAAUUGAACACCUUAGGUGACCGUGUUGGUCACUGUGGUAUCAAAAAUGCUACAUAUAUAAAGUGUAAUAUCUCAGAUGUCCAGUGUGGAAGAAUUCAGUGUGAGAAUGUGACAGAAAUUCCCAAUAUGAGUGAUCAUACUACUGUGCAUUGGGCUCGCUUCAAUGACAUAAUGUGCUGGAGUACUGAUUACCAUUUGGGGAUGAAGGGACCUGAUAUUGGUGAAGUGAAAGAUGGAACAGAGUGUGGGAUAGAUCAUAUAUGCAUCCACAGGCACUGUGUCCAUAUAACCAUCUUGAAUAGUAAUUGCUCACCUGCAUUUUGUAACAAGAGGGGCAUCUGCAACAAUAAACAUCACUGCCAUUGCAAUUAUCUGUGGGACCCUCCCAACUGCCUGAUAAAAGGCUAUGGAGGUAGUGUUGACAGUGGCCCACCCCCUAAGAGAAAGAAGAAAAAGAAGUUCUGUUAUCUGUGUAUAUUGUUGCUUAUUGUUUUGUUUAUUUUAUUAUGUUGUCUUUAUCGACUUUGUAAAAAAAGUAAACCAAUAAAAAAGCAGCAAGAUGUUCAAACUCCAUCUGCAAAAGAAGAGGAAAAAAUUCAGCGUCGACCUCAUGAGUUACCUCCCCAGAGUCAACCUUGGGUGAUGCCUUCCCAGAGUCAACCUCCUGUGACGCCUUCCCAGAGUCAUCCUCAGGUGAUGCCUUCCCAGAGUCAACCUCCUGUGACACCCUCCCAGAGUCAACCUCGGGUGAUGCCUUCUCAGAGUCAACCUCCUGUGAUGCCUUCCCAGAGUCAUCCUCAGUUGACGCCUUCCCAGAGUCAACCUCCUGUGACACCCUCCCAGAGGCAACCUCAGUUGAUGCCUUCCCAGAGUCAACCUCCUGUGACGCCCUCCUAGAGCCAACCUCAGUUGAUGCCUUCCCAGAGUCAACCUCCUGUGACGCCCUCCCAGAGCCAACCUCGGGUGACACCCUCCCAGAGUCAACCUCAUGUGACACCUUACCGGAGUAAAAGUGGUAAACAAAAGCAAUCAGUACCAAUUCCAAAAACUGUAUCCAGAAAAGGUACAUUAAAAAAAUAAUUCCUAGUA